GAUGUCCCAGAGUCAACAGCGAGCGAGCAGCCGGAGCGGGGAAGCAGAAGCCAGAGAGGGGAAGAAUACGGCGCCCCCUCUCUCCCUCCCCUCCCCCUUCUACUUUAGCCUUUCUGCGCACUUCGCUUCCAAGUCUCCGCGCAGCCAGGAGCCGCUGUUGCCUCCCAGCCCCUGCUAGCUGCCCCCCGAGCCGAGCGCAGCGAGCGCCGCCGCCCGGGCCCCCCGGUGGGGCCAGGGCCAGCAUGGAGCACCUGGGUCCGCACCACCUCCACCCGGGUCACGCAGAGCCCAUUAGCUUCGGCAUCGACCAGAUCCUCAACAGCCCGGACCAGGGUGGCUGCAUGGGACCCGCCUCGCGCCUCCAGGACGGAGAAUACGGCCUUGGCUGCUUGGUCGGAGGCGCCUACACUUACGGCGGCGGGGGCUCCGCGGCCGCGACGGGGGCUGGAGGAGCGGGGGCCUAUGGUACUGGAGGUCCCGGCGGCCCCGGAGGCCCGGCAGGCGGCGGCGGCGCCUGCAGCAUGGGUCCUCUGACCGGCUCCUACAACGUGAACAUGGCCUUGGCAGGCGGCCCCGGUCCUGGCGGCGGCGGCGGCAGCAGCGGCGGUGCCGGGGCACUCAGCGCUGCGGGGGUAAUCCGGGUGCCGGCACACAGGCCGCUCGCCGGAGCCGUGGCCCACCCCCAGCCCCUGGCCACCGGCUUGCCCACCGUGCCCUCUGUGCCUGCCAUGCCGGGCGUCAACAACCUCACUGGCCUCACCUUCCCCUGGAUGGAGAGUAACCGCAGAUACACAAAGGACAGGUUCACAGUGGCCCUCUCACCCUUCACUGUAACACGCCGUAUAGGUCACCCCUAUCAGAACCGGACGCCCCCCAAGAAGAAGAAGCCGCGCACGUCCUUCACACGCCUGCAGAUCUGCGAGCUGGAGAAGCGCUUCCACCGCCAGAAGUACCUGGCCUCGGCCGAGCGCGCCGCCCUGGCCAAGGCGCUCAAAAUGACCGAUGCGCAGGUCAAAACCUGGUUCCAGAACCGGCGGACAAAGUGGAGACGGCAGACUGCGGAGGAACGGGAGGCCGAGAGGCAGCAAGCGAACCGCAUCCUCCUGCAGUUGCAGCAGGAGGCCUUCCAGAAGAGCCUGGCACAGCCGCUGCCCGCUGACCCUCUGUGCGUGCACAACUCGUCGCUCUUCGCCCUGCAGAAUCUGCAGCCGUGGUCUGACGACUCGACCAAAAUCACUAGCGUCACGUCGGUGGCGUCGGCCUGCGAGUGAGCCUGCCCAUUCUGCCCUGUGGGACCCCAGGCCCACUCAGGGGUCACUGAGGCCUGAGACCCAGGACUCCUCCCCACCCUCCUGGCCUCAGACUGCACCCAGGAGGGGAACACUGCCCUCGCACGGCCCCGAAGGGCCCCCACAUUUGUGCCGACACUGUUCUCCCUUCGGUGGAAGAGCUCAAGGGACAAGGACACGCGCCCCCCUCCCAGAGGCGUCCCGCACCUGUCUGAACUGUUAAGAAAUCUGUUUUUGUUUAUUUCAUUUUAUUUUAAUUUUUAACGUGGGAUUCAGAGAAAGGCAAGGGAGGUAAGGGAGGAGGAGCUUCUGGGGUCCCCAGGGCUGUCAUCUGAAUUUGCCCUGGGAAACCCCUUCUCUGUGACCCACUUCUCAUCACACACAUGGAAACCCAUAGGCCCACACACAGGUGGUGUCACUGUCCCUCCUGGUGUCACCCCAGAGCCACACAUGGGCAUCUAUGGGAGAGUGUCAACCAGACAGAGGGUCACAGUGUUUACACUUUGGACCUUACGAUCAGGCACAGGUCAGGGGUGACACAGACUCAUCCUGAACAGCAUGGCACUCCCUCCAGCACAAACACAAGGUCAUGGCCACACUGUGACACACUACACCACACACAACAGCCAACAGCUACAACAGCCUCACUUGGUCUGCCAGGCCCCCACCACACAUCCCAGCCCAAUCCAGGUACGCACAGACAGGUUUUCACAUAAAUGCAGCCCAUUUCUCCAGAACCCAUUUGAGGGGUGGGGGGGUGUUAAUUUAUGCACUUAUAAGGUGUUUUCUGUGUAACCAUUUUAUAAAGUGCUUGUGUAAUUUAUGUGAAAAAAAUAAAUAAAAGCCUCCGGAUCCGGA